AGAAAGCGGCGCUGGGACCCUGAGGCGGCCGUGGUUAGGCGGCUCCCCGGCGGCUCCUCCGCGGCGGUGACGGCGACCGCACUCCCCGCUUCCCGCUCCCCGCGCUCCUCCGCCCGGGUCCGCCAGCCGAGGCCGCUCCCGAGCGUCGGAAGAUGCCGGCCGUGUCCAAGGGGGACGGGAUGCGGGGCCUGGCGGUCUUCAUCUCGGAUAUCCGCAACUCUCCGUGGUAACCAUGGAAACCAGCUGCCUUAUAACCAUGGUAGCUGGGAAAGCCAGCAGCCUAGCAGCUACUGGAGGGGACACAUGAAGGCUGGAGCUCCUCAGCAAGUCCCGGCUGCAGAGCAUGUCACUCUCGGACCUGUCCCACUUACUGAGCUUGCCAUCGUAUGAGCUAGCUCAGUGUGAAAACCCUGUUUCUGAAAGAGAGACUGUCAGUUGAGAAUUCUGUGUCCAGUAAAACUGUCCUUUGAAAAUAGAGGAAUUGGCUGGGUGUGGUGGCUCAUGCCUGUAAUCCCAGCACUUUGGGAGGCCAAGGUGGGUGGAUCAUCUGAGGUCGGGAGUUCGAGACCAGUCUGGCCAACAUGGUGAAACCCCGUCUCUACUAAAAAUACAAAAAUUAGCCAGGCGUGUUGGCGAACGCCUGUAAUUUAGCUACUCAGGAGGCUGAGUCACGAGAAUUGCUUGAACCUGGGAGGCGGAGGUUGCAGUGAGCCAAGAUUGUGCCACUGCACUCCAGCCUGGGUGAACAGAGCAAGAUCCUGUCUCAAAAAAAAAGAAAUUAAGAUAUUUCCAGGUAAACAAUAAACAGAGGACAUUUGUUGUUUUAGCCAACCUCCCUUAUAAUACAUACUGAAAGGAAUGUCUCAGGCUGGAAUGAAAGGACACUAGGUGGUAGGAUACGUGAAGAAAUAAAAGAACAACGGUGAAGACAGCUACAUAUGUCAAGUUAAAAGACAAUAAUUCCCACAUUUCAUGGGUGUGAGCUGAAAAAAAGACUUGAAGCUAACAUUCCUCUGCUGUCCCACUACAACACAGAAGACUUCUGUGACCCCAGAAUAUGUGGGGGUUUCUCCCCAUCGGCAAACAAGCUAUCAGUUCUGCAGCAGGCACCAGCGGGGUGUCCUCCAGCUUGAUUCUGACACCGUCUACCUGGAGGUAAAAGUAAAGAAGCAGAAAUAAAAAGGAUAAACAAGGAACUGGCAAAUAUCAGAUCAAAAUUUAAAGGUGACAAGGCUCUUGAUGGCUAUAGUAAAAAAAAGUACGUCUGCAAGUUGCUCUUCAUCUUUCUCCUUGGUCAUGACAUUGACUUUGGACACAUGGAGGCUGUGAACCUGCUGAGUUCAAACAGAUACACGGAAAAGCAGAUCGGCUACCUUUUCAUCUCUGUGUUGGUGAACUCAAACAGUGAGCUGAUCCGCCUGAUCAACAACGCCAUCAAGAAUGACCUGGCCAGCCGCAACCCCACCUUCAUGGGCCUGGCCCUGCACUGCAUCGCCAGCGUGGGCAGCCGGGAGAUGGCCGAGGCCUUCGCCGGGGAGAUCCCUAAGGUCCUCGUAGCCGGAGACACUAUGGACAGCGUGAAGCAGAGCGCGGCCCUGUGCUUGCUGCGCCUGUACAGGACGUCCCCCGAUCUUGUCCCCAUGGGCGACUGGACAUCCCGAGUGGUGCACCUGCUCAAUGACCAGCACUUGGGUGUGGUAACUGCAGCCACAAGUCUGAUCACCACUUUAGCACAGAAGAACCCAGAAGAGUUUAAAACCUCCGUGUCUCUGGCUGUCUCUAGGCUAAGCAGAAUCGUGACGUCUGCAUCCACAGAUCUCCAGGAUUACACUUACUAUUUUGUCCCGGCUCCCUGGCUGUCUGUCAAACUGCUGAGACUGCUGCAGUGCUACCCACCCCCAGAAGACCCUGCAGUGCGAGGCCGCCUGACUGAGUGCCUGGAGACCAUCCUGAACAAAGCCCAAGAACCGCCCAAGUCGAAGAAGGUCCAGCACUCCAACGCGAAGAAUGCCGUGCUCUUCGAGGCCAUCAGCUUAAUCAUUCACCAUGACAGUGAGCCGAACCUGCUCGUCCGUGCCUGCAACCAGUUGGGCCAGUUUCUGCAGCACCGCGAGACCAACCUGCGCUACCUGGCCCUGGAGAGCAUGUGCACGCUGGCCAGCUCUGAGUUCUCCCAUGAGGCUGUCAAGACGCACAUCGAGACGGUCAUCAACGCCCUGAAGACUGAGCGGGACGUGAGCGUGCGGCAGCGGGCCGUGGACCUCCUCUACGCCAUGUGCGACCGCAGCAACGCCCCACAGAUCGUGGCCGAGAUGCUGAGCUAUCUGGAGACAGCUGACUACUCCAUCCGAGAAGAGAUUGUGCUGAAGGUCGCCAUCCUGGCUGAGAAGUACGCGGUGGACUACACCUGGUAUGUGGAUACCAUCUUGAACUUGAUCCGAAUUGCUGGUGAUUACGUGAGUGAAGAGGUGUGGUACCGAGUCAUUCAGAUCGUCAUCAACCGGGACGACGUGCAGGGCUACGCGGCCAAGACUGUGUUCGAGGCUCUUCAGGCUCCCGCGUGCCACGAGAACCUGGUCAAAGUGGGCGGCUACAUCCUGGGGGAGUUUGGAAACUUGAUAGCUGGAGACCCGAGAUCCAGCCCGCUGAUCCAGUUCCACCUGCUGCACUCCAAGUUCCACCUGUGCAGCGUCCCCACCCGCGCGCUGCUCCUGUCCACCUACAUCAAGUUCGUGAACCUCUUCCCGGAGGUGAAGCCCACCAUCCAGGACGUGCUGCGCAGCGACAGCCAGCUCAGGAACGCAGACGUGGAGCUGCAGCAGCGUGCUGUGGAGUACCUGCGGCUCAGCACCGUGGCCAGCACCGACAUUCUGGCGACCGUGCUGGAGGAGAUGCCCCCAUUCCCGGAGCGGGAGUCCUCCAUCUUGGCAAAGCUCAAGAAGAAGAAGGGCCCCAGCACGGUGACAGACCUGGAGGACACCAAGCGGGACAGGAGUGUGGACGUGAACGGGGGUCCUGAGCCUGCCCCAGCCAGUACCAGCGCCGUGUCUACGCCUUCUCCGUCGGCAGACCUGCUGGGUCUCGGGGCUGCCCCCCCUGCCCCCGCGGGCCCCCCACCCUCCUCCGGCGGCAGCGGGCUGCUCGUGGACGUGUUCUCAGACUCGGCCUCUGUGGUCGCGCCUCUCGCUCCUGGCUCCGAAGACAACUUUGCCAGGUUUGUUUGUAAAAACAAUGGUGUGUUGUUUGAAAACCAGCUGCUUCAAAUUGGACUUAAGUCUGAAUUUCGGCAGAAUUUAGGUCGGAUGUUUAUCUUUUAUGGUAAUAAGACCUCCACGCAGUUCCUAAACUUUACCCCAACACUAAUCUGUUCAGACGACCUUCAGCCUAACCUGAACCUGCAGACCAAGCCCGUGGACCCGACCGUGGAGGGGGGCGCGCAGGUGCAGCAGGUGGUCAACAUAGAGUGCGUGUCCGACUUCACGGAGGCGCCAGUCCUCAACAUUCAGUUCAGGUAUGGGGGCACCUUCCAGAACGUGUCUGUGCAGCUGCCCAUCACUCUCAACAAAUUCUUCCAGCCGACAGAAAUGGCUUCUCAGGAUUUCUUUCAACGUUGGAAGCAGUUGAGCAAUCCACAGCAGGAAGUGCAGAACAUCUUCAAAGCAAAGCACCCAAUGGACACAGAAGUCACCAAAGCCAAGAUCAUUGGAUUUGGUUCUGCACUUCUUGAAGAAGUUGAUCCUAAUCCUGCGAAUUUCGUGGGAGCUGGAAUCAUCCACACGAAAACCACCCAGAUUGGAUGCCUGCUGCGCUUGGAGCCGAACCUGCAAGCCCAGAUGUACCGGCUCACGCUGCGCACAAGUAAGGAAGCCGUUUCUCAGAGAUUAUGUGAAUUGCUCUCAGCGCAGUUUUAGUCCUGAGGAUGGAAGACCAGGCUCGUGUGUCUUGUGUUGUCUUCGUCUGUGCCGUUUGUCUUCGUGGCCAUCCUGCAGAUGAGCACCGUGUCCAGUGCCACAGCACAAGGCGCCUCCCCGCCCCGCCGCCCCACACCUCUCCCCUUUGGGCUGGACGGGAACACACGUGUGUGGCUCAGGAGGAAAAGCUCAGCCUGGACUGUGGCAGCCACGGCAGAAGGUGGAUCUUGGGAUCAAUUUUUAUAAAAAUCGAGACAGUUCUGUGGUUAAAUCUACAAAUUAAAGGGAAAUUAGAAGUUGGCGUGAACGUGGCGUUUGUGGGAGUGUCACUGAGAUGGCCCGUGCUGCCGCCCACCCCGCCUCGGAGCCUCUGGGAGCAGCAGUGCCACUGUGCAUGGCGUGGGCUGAGCCUUGGUGUGUGGCCGUCCUGGUGGCUGCACACCUGGCGUCGUCCUGGGCCCUUGGGAGGAGCACAGCUGACCCUGGUUUUGCUGCAGUCCCAGCUGGACUGUUUUCCCAGGCAGGAUUUUAAUCUAGAAUUUAGAAACAUUUGUAUUUGUAAUGACUUCUGGCAAAAGCACGUGUCCUGGCCGGAUGUAACUGUUCUCCUUUCCCAGCUCCUGUUUGUGAAGGGCGUCUGUUAUGCUCCUGCAGUCGCCGAGGCCUUGGAUGUGCAGCCAGGGGAGGAGCGUCCUGCCGGCCCCGCAGGGCCCCCAGGACUCCAGGGUAAAGUGUGGGCCGGUGGCGCAAGACUCAGAGGUGUGCUCGUCUCUUUCCUGUCAGAGUGGGCGUCCCCAGGCCACGGUGCAGGCCUGAGUCCUUCCACCGGCCCCGUCCAGUCGUCCCUGGAGGGGCUGUGGAGGAGGGACGCCUCUGUGUGGUCAGGAAGUGAAGGGGCCAUUGGCCGCAUGCCAUGUGCCACCUGCGGCUUGUGUCUCACCUGUCAUCUGGACUCAGCACCCAGGCUGCACGUCUGACACCUGAGAGGCGAGAGAGUGGGGCCGGCCUAGGAGCCAAGGCUGGGGCCUUGCGCUCUGUCCCCAGGAUGGUGGCCUUGUUUGUCCUAAACACACCCAGCACAGGUUCUGGCUUCCUGACAUGCUGUGGAGGCAGGGAGGGUGGGUGGCCACAUGUGCUUGAGGGUUUUCACCCUGGCCCUCAGUUGCCUGCUGUGCGGGUCCCUGGGGCAGCUGCAGGGGCUCAUGGACCCAUCAGGGUCUCCACAGCUCCCCUGCAGUGUGUGCACCCCACAAUGUCUGCGGCUCUUCUUCCGGCGUGUCGGGCUUUGAUCACAGCAUAGCCACGUCAGUGGCGUGCGCCUCUCGCACAGGCCAUUCUGGGUCUGGUGGUGCCAGGUGCCGUGACACGCCGUGCUGGGCUUGUGCUGCAGCUGGGUGGUGUGGCCCUCAUUCUCAUGUUCCAGCUGCUGGGCAGUGCUCUGCCUGUGUGCUGCGCCUGCAGGCUGCGUGUGCUGCCGUGGAUCUCCUGCAUCCCUUGACCCCUCCCGCCAUCAGAGGAAAGGCUGCUCCCCGAGGCACCGCUUCCCUGUGCGGCGCUGCAGAGGGGCCCUCAGUGUGGCACUCCUCGUCAAAGAAAAAUAAAGGCUAGAACUGCA